GGCAGAAUUUUCUUUCUCACUUGCCAGGGAGCCAUUCCUUCUGCAGCUGUCUCGCAGGCAUGGACAACCUGCGCGAGACUUUCCUCAGCCUCGAGGAUGGCUUGGGCUCCUCUGACAGCCCUGGCCUGCUGUCUUCCUGGGACUGGAAGGACAGGGCAGGGCCCUUUGAGCUGAAUCAGGCCUCCCCCUCUCAGAGCCUUUCCCCGGCUCCAUCGCUGGAAUCCUAUUCUUCUUCUCCCUGUCCAGCUGUGGCUGGGCUGCCCUGUGAGCACGGCGGGGCCAGCAGUGGGGGCAGCGAAGGCUGCAGUGUCGGUGGGGCCAGUGGCCUGGUAGAGGUGGACUACAAUAUGUUAGCUUUCCAGCCCACCCACCUUCAGGGCGGUGGUGGCCCCAAGGCCCAGAAGGGCACCAAAGUCAGGAUGUCUGUCCAGCGGAGGCGGAAAGCCAGCGAGAGGGAGAAGCUCAGGAUGAGGACCUUGGCAGAUGCCCUGCACACCCUCCGGAAUUACCUGCCACCUGUCUACAGCCAGAGAGGCCAGCCUCUCACCAAGAUCCAGACACUCAAGUACACCAUCAAGUACAUCGGGGAACUCACAGACCUCCUUAACCGCGGCAGAGAGCCCAGAGCCCAGAGCGCGUGAGCUCCAUCCGGGGAAACUGACCGGUUCCAGCCUCCUGAGCAGGAGUAGAGGAGUUUUGAAGACCUGGAUAUCUUAUUGAACAAUGAUCGGCGUAGAGUGAUUUUUAUGUAGUAAGCCUGAUAAUCUUGUGAUCUGAAAAACCCUAAGGGAAUUCACAUGUAACCUGUUGGACCCACCAGAACACUUACCUGCCAGAUGAGCAGAGACUUUCACCUCCAGUUUUUUCCACCCAUCUGGGAGGCUCAUCCUUUGCAAACAGACAGAUUAUUUUGCCCUUCUCUGUCUGUUCAAGGUAUUUUAAAGGGUCAGUGAUUUUAAAUGCAUUUUUUUCAAUAAUGUAAAAGUGUUAAUCUCUUGCCAUUUUGGCGUUGAGACCUUUUCUUCUGUUGCUAACAAAACCUGUAUUUUGUAUAGGAUCCAGUGUGAUAUCUGGAUUCUUAUUUAGAAAGAUUUGUGCCAAGUAAAGGGCUUUAGUGCUCCUGUUUUCAUUUCGUGUGUAUAUGUGUGUGUGUUUGUGUUUGACUGAAAUCAUGCUGUUGCAGGGACCAAAAUCACUUAAAUGCGGAAGGCACUGGUGUCAUGAUAAAUGGAAAGUCACAGGCAGACAGGCUAAGUUAAGACAGUGAAGAUUCCAAAAGCCAGAGCCUCCUCUUCACAGGCAAACAGCUUGUGUGACAGGGAAGGAGGGUACGGGGAGG